GUUACAGUAAAGCUUAGGUUUUGAAAAAAGUCAAGAUCUCAGCAUUUAGCAACAGAAAAUAUUUGUGCUGAAAGUCCCAAGAAUUAGGAGUUGCUGUUGUUGACCUUUACAGUAAAAAUAUUUCUGUCUUCUUCCUCUUUUAUGUAUCUGAAGGUAACAGAACGUUGGCUGGAAUAGAAAAUAUCUUAAGCCUGUUAUCUCUUCAAUUAAAAGUCUCUAUUAAUAUGACCUGGCUGUGCAGCUAUUUGUAAAUAUAACUGUCUGGUCUUUUCCUGCAUAGCAUAAGCUAAUAGGUAUGUUACUUAGAUGGGGAUUUACUCAAAGAAAUGCUAGUCUUUAUUCUUUUCUUUAUAUUUUAGAUGAGCCCUCACAUAUUAAGAUAACCUCUACUGAAUGCAUACUGUGGGCUAGAUGCUUUGUAUGCAUUAUGUCAUUUAAUCCUUACAGGAGGAUAAUGUUAUAGCCAUUGUAUAAGUGUGGGGACUAAGAGAGCUAAGUAAAUUACCCAAGGCCACACAGCUAGUGGUAAGUGAUAAAGCUGGGAUUCAAACCCAGAUAGCAGGCUUUGAGCCUAAGUUCUUAACCACUAUCCCCAUGUGGUAUAAUGAUUACUUGAGUCAAUUCCAAUAGCUUCCUAAAGGGAGUUAAACUCCACCUAGUGUACCAGGAUUCGUCUUGCCCCUUUUUAUCCCAUAUUGUAUAUUUGUACCAUGUGCAGCUUUCCUACACUCACCACACAGCACCACCAUGGGUGUGCGUGUCCGUCUCCCCCACCCCUCGUGGCCAUUCUCAGUCUGUUCUGUGGUCCAGUGGCUCUGCAGUCAGGUACAAGCCAGUCUACUUUCUGAAGAAAUUUAGCUAAUGCUGUAAAUCCUUUGAGUGAAUGUGUUUAAAUAAGUCUCCCAAUGUCAAGCCUGCAUAAAUAUAUUUCUCUAUUUGCAUUAUGAGGAGAGGAUAGCUUUUAAAUUUAGAACGUUAAACCAGCAAAUUGUUAGUAUAUUGCUCCUGGGCCUAAAGGGGCAUUUGAUUUAGCUGGGGUGGGAGUUAGGAAGAGAGUCGGACAUAAUCAUCUACCUGUGGUGAUUACAUAGAUUUAAGCGUGUCCCAGAGACCCAACCAGACAUGCUGUAGGAGUGUAUUCAUUCAACAGAUACUUAAUUUACAAAGCGUUUACCCAGGGCCCCACGUUCACGGGCAGCAGGAGAUGGCAGGUUACCCUGAUGGACACAGCCCUUCUCUGUGUCCUUCUAAUGGAGCUCAGACGAGAGUGAUUGUAUAUGUCGAUUUUGUUUGUUGCAUUUUCCAAUGUUUGUUAAAAUUUCAAGCAUAGAAGAGUUAAACGAAUUUCAUAGUGAAUAAUCAUAUACCCACCUUCUAGAUUUUACCAUUCCCAUUUUACUGCUCUUGCUUUCUCUCAUAUUUGCCCAUUCCUCCAUCUCCUGUGCCUGUCUGUAUCAUCCACUUUCAGAACUCAGACACUGUUAUUUUAAGGGUACUCAUAGUGUCACAUGCUAAAAAUUCUUUUUUCUUUCUCUUUUUUUUUUUUUUUUUUUUUUGAGACAGAGUCUCACUCUGUCACCCAGGCUGGAGUGUAGUGGUGUGAACUCGGCUCACUGCAACCUCCGCCUUCCAGGUUCAAGCGAUUCUCCUGCUUCAGCCUCCCAAGUAGCUGGGAUUAUAGGCUCCUGCCACCACACCCGGCUUUUUGUAUUUUUAAUAGAGAUGGGGUUUCACCAUGUUGGCUAGGCUGGUCUCAAACUCCUGACCUCAAGUGAUCCUCCUGCCUCAGCCUCCCAAAAUGUUGGGAUUACAAGUGUGAACCGCUGCGCCUGGCCAAAAAUCAUUUUUUCUGUAGUCACAUGCUGAAAAUCACUUAUUCUGUGAUCGACCACAACAAGUUAAUUUUUUCAAAAAGACUCAAUUUAGUCUUUUUAUACAUAAGGCAAAGUCUUAGUAUACAUAGUCUUAGUAUACAUAAGGCAAAUCUGAUUUCCUCCUUUUGGUGAUCAUGUCAUGAAGGUUAGAGGUCUGACAAAGAGUAAGAUAUAUUUCAUACAAAUGAUCAAGAACAUCACAUUUAAAAUAUUUGAGUCCUUGCCACUUUAUGCAAGGCAUUUGGAGAAUCUUUUGGGGGAAACAUUCUCCGGGUAAGACAGAGCUGUCCCCGUGAUUCACUGGUGGGACUGACCAUCUGAUUUGCAAAUAAUGAAGAAAGUGAAAGGAGGCGGCUGGAUGUCAGCCAGCAGGCUGUGGGAAGGCCAGAGCCCUUCUGAUGGGGUAGGGCUUUGCUAAAUUGAGGAAGAUGAGGUGUGCAGAUAAGAGUACAGUAUAGUGUGAGGAACAGCAGAGAUGUAGAAAAGUUUGGGGAAAUGUGUGAAGUUUGAAGCUUCAGAGUGAAGGUUAGUGGCAGGUAGGGAGAAUGGGGAAUGCAGCACGAGGCAAAGUUGAGACCUGUGCUGAAGAAACUCCUGAUUGAGCCACAGGAAGCUUGGAGGUGACUCUAGGGGCAGUGAGUGCUAAUGAAGGGAUUUUAAUUACCCAUGAUGGACAGUUAAGAGCUUUGCAAAAUAAGGAGUGGGAAGAGAAAGAGGAUGAAGAUGCUGCUCAGUAGAAAGGAAGAGGAGGGAAAGGUGGAAGGAAAGGACAGAGAGGCGCCACAGGAUGGAAACCUCAGCCCAGGAGCUGAAUAGGUUUUACCGUGACGAGGUGUCUGUAGUUAGGGAACUACCAAGGGGAUUUGGGAGUUGAGAGUGAAGAAGGCAGAGAUCGACGUAUGGGAAGGAUGGGUUCAGAGAGAAAGCCAGUGAUUGGUUACAGUUAAGAGGGGAAGGGACCUGCCAGGGCAGUAAAAGGCCAUCUGCUGAGGGACUGAGUCCGAGGGCCGUGACGGAAGCUGCAGGAAAGAUCUCCAGUUGGUAGGGUUUUGAGAAAUGUGUUAUCAGCAGGAGUUGGGUUGAAACAAGAUAAAGAGAGCGUUCCAGGAAAAAAAAAAACAAAACCAAAGAGAUAGAAACAAACAUAACCACAAAGAUUUCAUAACUUAGGUGGAGAGCUAAGAUCACAUACAUAACCAACUAGUAUGACAGUUACUACACACCUACAAAUUAUUGACCAAGUGAUUUUCAAAGAACAAUUAUUUGUUUUUGCCCUAAUUAAAUGGAUUUUAAUUUUUUGAGGACACUUGCUAUGAAUAGUUCACCUCCAGGUUUUUCCUCCAUCUUGAUGAAAAUCCUUCCUGGCCAGUUUGCUAAGACUGAACUGUCUUCUGGAAGGCCCCAGCGAACAUUCACUCUCCUGUUCUAGCUCACAGUCCUGUGUUCCUUUGUGAUGUACCUCACUUAGCUUCUGGCAGUCUUCUGAAUCCAGACCACUCACUUCUGAACUCUAGCCCGAGGUUACACAGCGGAAGAGAGGUAGAGCUGUUAACGGAAUUCCAACUCACUAGGCUCUUGACUGUGGCCCUCCGAGCCCCUCCAUUUCACAGCCGGUCCUUGAUGGAAACCAGGCUGAGGCUGCUGUACCAAUGAUAGUCUGUCCCUAGUGUCCCAAACUUUGGUACUUUUUCAAGUUCUUAUUUGAAAAAACUUGUAACUUAGAGUUUGGAGGACACGGAAUAUAUUGCUAAAUAGGAGAAUAAAACUACAUUUCCUUAAAGAAAACUGUAGAAGGAAGGGUUUCUCUUAGCUGAAGUGUGACUGCCAGGCCCUCAGCAUGAUUGCCUUCAUUUCCAGCGUCCACUGGGGUCAUCUGAGAGUCCAUCCCGAAGCCGAAUGUCACCUUGUAAAGCUGUGUGUUUGAGAAGUCACAGUCUUGUGGAUGAAACAUCUUUCUCCUGUUGGCAGUGGCAAUGACCCCUGGUCAGCCUGGAGUGCCUCCAAAUCUGGGAACUGGGAAAGCUCAGAAGGCUGGGGGGCCCAGCCAGAGGGGGCUGGAGCCCAAAGAAACACAAACACUCCCAACAACUGGGACACUGCCUUCGGCCACCCCCAGGCCUACCAAGGACCAGCAACUGGUGAUGAUGAUGACUGGGAUGAAGACUGGGAUGGGCCCAAAUCCUCUUCCUACUUUAAGGAUUCAGAGUCAGCUGAUGCAGGCGGCGCUCAGCGAGGAAACAGUCGUGCUAGUUCCUCAUCCAUGAAAAUUCCCCUUAACAAAUUUCCUGGAUUUGCGAAACCUGGCACGGAACAGUAUUUGUUGGCCAAACAACUAGCAAAACCCAAAGAGAAAAUUCCCAUCAUUGUUGGAGAUUAUGGCCCAAUGUGGGUUUAUCCUACCUCUACUUUUGACUGUGUGGUAGCAGAUCCCAGGAAAGGCUCCAAAAUGUAUGGUCUAAAGAGCUACAUCGAAUAUCAGCUAACACCUACUAACACUAAUCGAUCUGUAAACCACAGGUAUAAGCACUUUGACUGGUUAUAUGAGCGUCUCCUGGUUAAGUUUGGGUCAGCCAUUCCAAUCCCUUCUCUUCCAGACAAACAAGUCACAGGCCGCUUUGAAGAGGAAUUUAUCAAAAUGCGCAUGGAGAGACUUCAGGCCUGGAUGACCAGGAUGUGUCGCCAUCCAGUAAUCUCAGAAAGUGAAGUUUUCCAGCAGUUCCUAAAUUUCCGAGAUGAGAAGGAAUGGAAAACUGGAAAGAGGAAGGCCGAGAGAGAUGAGCUGGCGGGAGUCAUGAUAUUUUCCACCAUGGAACCAGAGGCACCUGACUUGGACUUAGUAGAAAUAGAGCAGAAGUGCGAGGCUGUGGGGAAGUUCACCAAGGCCAUGGAUGACGGCGUGAAGGAGCUGCUGACGGUGGGGCAGGAGCACUGGAAGCGCUGCACGGGCCCAUUACCCAAGGAAUAUCAGAAGAUAGGAAAGGCCUUGCAGAGUUUGGCCACAGUGUUCAGUUCCAGUGGCUAUCAAGGUGAAACAGAUCUCAAUGAUGCAAUAACAGAAGCAGGAAAGACUUAUGAAGAAAUUGCCAGUCUCGUGGCAGAACAGCCAAAGAAAGAUCUCCAUUUCCUGAUGGAAUGUAAUCACGAGUAUAAAGGUUUUCUUGGCUGCUUCCCUGACAUCAUUGGCACUCACAAGGGAGCAAUAGAAAAAGUGAAAGAAAGUGACAAACUAGUUGCAACAAGUAAAAUCACCCUACAAGACAAACAGAACAUGGUGAAGAGAGUCAGCAUCAUGUCUUACGCGUUGCAAGCUGAGAUGAAUCACUUUCACAGUAACCGGAUCUAUGAUUACAACAGUGUCAUCCGCCUGUACCUGGAGCAGCAAGUGCAAUUUUACGAAACGAUUGCAGAAAAGCUGAGGCAGGCCCUCAGCCGCUUUCCAGUGAUGUAGGACAGAACGGGCCUUGAAGAGAAUGCCGCGUGCUUUCUCCUGACUUGGGGCAAUGCAAUUCAAAACUUUUUUUCCCCUAUUAUUCAGAAAAAAAAGGAAACAAAACCAAAAAGAAAGAGUUGCAAAAAACUGCAUUUAUUUUAUUAGCCACCCUAAAUGCGUCAGUUAUUUAGGGAUGGUCUUUUGUUCAUUUCCGCAUCCAUUAUUUAAACCAGUGGAAAUUGUCUCUAUUUUUGGAAAGUACUUAAAAGUUACCAGAAUUUUCAAUGGAAAAUGAGGGGUUUCUCCCCACUGAUAUUUUACAUAGAGUCAUAAUUUAUAUGUCUUAUAAAUUAUAAGUCUUAUAUAAUUUAUAAGUCUCCCACAAUCUUCCAGUUCUUACCCAGUGUCAGAUAAUUAAUUACUAAUUACUUUCUUAAAAACAUGAACUAUGCCAGAAUAAAAAAUAUCUAUGUUUGUAUAUUUUUAUAACUCCUUUCAGUCCUCUGGGGCUCCUGUCAUUGAGGGAAGUCGUUACGCCUUUCACUGCCACAGUUACAGCUCAAGUGCUUACACUUCAAGAGGGAGGACGCUGGGGGCCCCUGGGGCUGCUAGUGCCAUCGUGGUGUGUGGCAGGUGGGCCAUCCCAUGUCCCUCCAGGGGGACCCCACAGCCUGGCAGAUGAGCAGAUACCCCUGGCCACCCAUGUCCUCAGCGACAUUUCUGAUGUGCUGCUCUUAUGUGAGGACCAGUGCUUUCUCUCUUUGCACUUCCUUCCUAAUCUUGGUUAAGGCAUGUUUUAUGCCAUGAAGAAUACAUUAGAAGAAUUGAGGGACUUUGUAGAGAAUUUUGUGGCUUUGGUCCAACGGGUGAGUGGCUGUGCGGAGGCCUGUGUUCGGGAGGGCCUGGGAGAAGGAGGGCACCCAGCACCCCGGCGUCUCUGGCCCUUUCUUAUUCUUUGGCUCCUCAUCCACCGUGAUGAGAAGCGCUGCUGUGGCCACGGCACACUGCUUGGCUUGGGUGGCGGGUUCAUGGCCAGUUGGUGUCAUCAGCAAAGAGAAAAAGCACAGGUUAGCUCCCCAUUAGAUGGAAAAGUGUAGGGACUGAGAAGGGCUGCAGCCUCAGCAGUGUACAGAGUCCCCGGCGCUCUGAGGUUGGAGAGAAAGAACAGACCAGCGCCCUUCCCGACUACAUCCGAAACUUCACACAGGGUGUUUCUGAGCACCAGCACUUCCAGCGCUUCACUUAACGGCAUAAAGCAAAACAGGACCUUGGCACACCGUCAGCUCGAACUCAACACUGGCAGCCACCGUCUCACCCCUGCGGAGGAGCGCUCCCGUCUCCCACAGGUGCCUUACCGCGUUCCCUCCCGCUGCUUUCAUUUUUCUGACCUAAUAAUUACGGGAAAUGGAAAGUCUGGGCCAGCAUCAAUAAAAUGACACCAAAAAUAAGUAGAUGAAAUCAAAUGAAUAUGAGAACAUCUUGUUCUUCAAUAUCACGGGUUUUUGUUAAUGUUUCAUAAGUAAUUCUCCCCACUUGAUUUUUCUUCUAUAAAAUCCCAUAGAACAAUGUUUAUGCUAUAGCCAUUUAAUAUAUGUACAAAUUGUAAAGAAUAUGUAUAAAUGUUUUACACGAAUGUAAGAGCAUGUAGAAGCCAACAUAUAAAUAAAUUGUUUAAAAAAACUGUACAGUAAAUUCUCAAAGCACUUUUUCAAAACACUUUUUGGACUUUGUGUGUGAUUUUUGUUGUUGUUGUUAAGUACUUUUUAUUCCAGCUGCUGAAAAUGGUCCAGGUAAUGAAUUCUUCCCCAAAUCCUAUUUCUUCUGACAUGAAUUCAUCAUUUCAGUUCCGUAGGUCAGUGUUGCGGUCCGGGAAGCGUAUCAUAACCACCUGGGAGUUGCCAAGAAGCAGACAGUCUCCCAGUGUCUGACUCUCGGAUAUUUGGAUUUGACUGGUGUGAGGCAAAGUGAAAAAGGGAUGGGGGAAAUGGAGAUGGCACGGGCUCCUCAGAGCGUGGUAGCCGACUGUGAGGAAAAGCAGAGGGAAUGUGAAAGAAAAUAAGAGAAUCCACGGGAUUUGAUGCCUGGAAGAUUCUCCUUCAAGUGGCAACAUGGCAUAUAUAUCCUUCUCCGGGGAGUCACAUGCACCAUUUGGUUCUUAGAUACGUUGAUGUUUUGAUUUUUAAUGAUUUGUAUCAACCUGUAGGUACCACAGAAGAGCUGUAGUCAUACAAUCACAUAACUUUUACAAAUAUAGUGG